CUCUUUUCUGUCUGGCCCGCGGCCCCGCUGCCUGCCCUGCUCCAGGCUCCACCUGCGCCGCCGAUCGCCCGGGUAUCGCGGGGGCCCAGGCCAGCUGAGUCCGUUUUCCGCGCCGGGGUGGCGCCCCUCCAACCGUCCUAACGCCGGGCCGGCAGCAAGGAGUGUUCCUGGGACCUCAGAGACCAGGCUCAGAGCCUGACAUCCCUGCGAGGGGACAGCCUCAUCCGCCCAGGCCAGUGGGGGUCUCUACAAGUGCCCAGGCUCAGGUGCAGCCCCCAGCAAUGCAUCGCCGGAGACUGGCCCUGGGUCUGGGGUUCUGCCUGUUGGCGGGCACAAGCCUCAGUGUCCUGUGGGUGUAUCUUGAGAACUGGCUGCCAGUCUCCUAUGUCCCCUAUUAUCUCCCCUGCCCAGAGAUCUUCAACAUGAAGCUGCACUACAAGAGGGAGAAGCCACUCCAGCCCGUGGUAUGGUCACAGUACCCUCAGCCCAAGCUGCUGGAGCACAGGGGAGGGUCUCAGUGCCCACGGCCCCCCUGCUGCCAGGCCCACACAGCUGCUGACACUCACACCCUGGUUGGCGCCCAUCGUCUCCGAGGGAACCUUCAACCCAGAGCUUCUGCAGCACAUCUACCAGCCACUGAACCUGACCAUUGGGGUCACGGUGUUUGCCGUGGGGAAGUACACUCAUUUCAUCCAGUCCUUCCUGGAGUCAGCCGAGGAGUUCUUCAUGCGUGGGUACCGGGUGCACUACUACAUCUUCACUGACAACCCUGCAGCCGUUCCCGGGGUCCCGCUGGGUCCCCACCGGCUUCUCAGCUCCAUCCCCAUCCAGGGUCACUCCCACUGGGAGGAGACAUCCAUGCGCCGGAUGGAGACCAUCAGCCAGCACAUUGCUAAGAGGGCUCACCGGGAGGUGGACUACCUCUUCUGCCUUGAUGUGGACAUGGUGUUUCGGAACCCGUGGGGCCCUGAGACCUUGGGAGACCUGGUGGCUGCCAUUCACCCAAGCUACUACGCCGUUCCCCGCCAGCAGUUCCCCUAUGAGCGCAGGCGUGUUUCCACUGCCUUUGUGGCAGACAGCGAAGGGGACUUCUAUUAUGGUGGGGCAGUCUUCGGGGGGCAGGUGGCCAGGGUAUAUGAGUUUACUAGGGGCUGCCACAUGGCCAUCCUGGCGGACAAGGCCAAUGGCAUCAUGGCUGCCUGGCGGGAGGAAAGCCACCUGAACCGUCACUUCAUCUCAAACAAGCCGUCCAAGGUGCUGUCCCCCGAGUACCUCUGGGACGACAGGAAGCCCCAGCCACCCAGCCUGAAGCUGAUCCGCUUUUCUACACUGGACAAGGAUAUCAGCUGCCUGAGGAGCUGACCACGGAGCUGGGGGUUGCCAUGGAUGGGGACCCAAAGACCUGCAGCCACCAGUGCUUCACUAGCGUGCAGACCAGCCCUGUCCCGCCUCCCUGUCAGUCAGGCGAAUUCAACCGGAAAAGGGACGUGGAAAGGCCACUGUGAACUGCAGAGGGCUGUGCACACAGUAGCACACAGGAUCUCACAGUAACGCGGCAUGGGAACAGUGAGACAGGGGGAGGGGAGGCGCAGUUACAAAGGCAGGGCCCGGCAGGCUUGCCACGUUCUGCAGCCGUGCCUUUGCGGGGCAGGCUCUGAAGCCUCAGCCCGACUCAGAGUGCCUGAACCCUGCCGCGCCAGUCCCCCGUUUAUUGCAUAUUGCCCUUAACGUAGCAUUUCUAAUACCCUGGUGUGAAGGCGCCCUAGACCCCUUUUCUCUGGUCACAGGGGUCCUGGGUCCUUUGAUGUCUCCCAACCACAUGUAGCCAAUUCCUCACUCAGGCCCCCAGAGUGAGCCUUUGAAAUGGAACAGGUCUAGGCUCCCUCGGUUUCCUGCACCCCAAAGUGAGCCGCACUCUCAGGGGACUAGCCACCUCCUUCUUAAGAGGGUUUGGGGCAGUUUAUAAUAAAGGGGGCGUGUGCUCAACCCUA